AGGCGCCGGCCGCUGCGCUGCAGAUGGCGGAAAUGGAUCCGGUAGCCGAGUUCCCCCAGCCUCCCGGUGCUGCGCGCUGGGCUGAGGUUAUGGCUCGCUUCGCGGCCAGGCUGGGCGCGCAGGGCCGGCGGGUGGUGUUGGUUACGUCAGGCGGCACCAAGGUCCCACUGGAAGCGCGGCCGGUGCGCUUCCUGGACAACUUCAGCAGCGGGCGGCGCGGUGCAACCUCGGCCGAGGCCUUCCUAGCCGCCGGCUACGGGGUCCUGUUCUUGUAUCGCGCUCGCUCUGCCUUCCCCUAUGCCCACCGCUUCCCACCCCAGACUUGGCUGUCCGCUCUGCGGCCUUCGGGCCCAGCCCUUUCGGGCUUGCUGAGCCUGGAGGCCGAGGAGAAUGCACUUCCGGGUUUUGCUGAGGCUCUGAGGAGCUACCAGGAGGCUGCGGCUGCAGGCACCUUCCUGGCAGUAGAGUUCACCACUUUGGCGGACUAUUUGCAUCUGUUGCAGGCUGCGGCCCAGGCACUCAAUCCGCUAGGUGCGUGCCCUAGGAGUACCCCUUUUGCCUGGAAGCACAGCCUUUCUUUCCAGCCACUUAUCCCCUUACCUCCUGCUUACCCACGGAUCUCAGCUGGGGAACCCGAGUUGAGAAGGAGCUGAUCCUAUAUCGUACCUCGCCGAUUUGUUAACACCUUGUGUUUCUCUUUGCAGGCCCUUCUGCGAUGUUUUACCUGGCUGCGGCUGUGUCAGAUUUCUAUGUUCCUGUCUCUGAAAUGCCUGAACACAAGAUCCAGUCAUCUGGGGGCCCACUGCAGAUAACAAUGAAGAUGGUGCCAAAACUGCUUUCUCCUUUGGUUAAAGAUUGGGCUCCCAAAGCAUUUAUAAUUUCCUUUAAGUUGGAGACUGACCCCGCCAUUGUAAUUAAUCGAGCUCGGAAGGCUUUGGAAAUUUAUCAGCAUCAAGUGGUGGUGGCUAAUAUCCUUGAGUCACGACAGUCCUUUGUGUUUAUUGUAACCAAAGACUCGGAAACCAAGUUAUUGCUAUCAGAGGAAGAAAUAGAAAAAGGCGUAGAGAUAGAAGAGAAGAUAGUGGAUAAUCUUCAGUCUCGACACACAGCUUUUAUAGGUGACAGAAACUGAAGUAAAAAGCCCUUAUAGGAUCAAAAAUUGUUCAGGGCUCUUAGAGAUGGUGAAAACUACAAAAAAAACCAUGGCUUUCAUAUGGACAGAUAAAAUGAAAGAAAGGGAAAAGGCAGUGGUGUGUAGGCAAAUAUGGUUUGGCAUUUGUCUUUUAAUGACACCUGAUAUGAUGUCAUUUUGAUUUUGAAAUUGAACACUAGAACUGUUAAUCACCUUUAAAAAGAAGAGCUUAUUGGGAAUUAUAUAUUCCUUAAAAUAUACAUGGGGGCCUGAAUGUCAGCCAUCUUUAUACUAUAGAAAAAGGAUUAUGGAUGCAUGAAUGGUCAUGCUUUGGAGAUCAAAUAUUGGUUGAAUGCCUAUGUAUGUCAGGCCCUGUGCUGAGCCAUGAGGAUUAAAAAGAUGAAUAAACAUAUCUUGUUUAGGAAAUGGAUGUAUAAAAAAAUCAAGUGCAAUAAAGUGUGUGUCCAAAAGCUGACACAAUGGAAAGGAUGUUUUGUUUUGUUUGAAAUUUAUCAAAUAUAGUAGUAGGAAAGAAGGAUACCUCCCUGAAGAUAGAUUGUAGAAUGGUGAGCUUUUCACUGCAUUUACUUUUUGCUUCUUAUUGUAGAUUCACCUCAUGUUUGGGUAAUAGUUUACAUUUCAAGUAUUUUAGGACUGCUUUUCAGUUUAACUUAAUAUGUCCUUCCACCUGGGACCAGGCAGGGGCCACUUGGUGAUCUCUGUCCUGAGGGAUGCAUUACAGUGUGGUAGAGUAUGGGCUAGAAGUCAACUUAGCCAGCUGUGCCACCUAUUAGCUUUAUAAACUUAGGCAUUUGACUUAAUCUCAGUGUCCACAUGCAUAAAAUGAGGAUAAUCUCUCUGCAAAGUAAUGCCAUUUAUUGUGAGGAUCAAAUGAAAUAGCAAAAAGAAAGCAUCAGUCUGGUGCCUAGCAUUUGAUUCACACUCACUAAAUGGUUGCAAUUAUUGUUUUUCUCACUUAGCAAAGCAGUGUUACACCACUGCCCUGCUUAAUCUUUGAAUCCUUGAGAAUCUUUGAAAAACUUUCAAUACUUCUCUUGCUGUCCUACGUUUUGGGUUUGGAGUGCACAAGUAGCAUAGUGCAAAAAAAUUCCCUAAAUGAUCUGUAGGAUAGUCCAGGUGCAAUUUGAAAAAUUAGCAUUGAUGACUAAGGUAGAAGCAGGUACUGUGUUUCACAUAAAUAUUUGACUUAAAAUACAAUUCAUGGUGUUUCAUGGAGUAGGGAAGGGUAGCCCCUGUGUCUGUCUGAUAAUAGAAGUACAAUAAAUUUAAUUGAGAAGAUUUGACAGAAA